ACGUGGCCGGGAGACGCACAGGGCGCCAGCGUCGCCGCGAGGCCUCUGGGGUGGGUUCGCCAGGAGGGCACGUUCGCGCCGCGCCGCGGAGGGAGGCUGAGAGGGCCGGGCCGGGCGGCGGGGACACGGCGGUACCGUCCUGCGCUCGGGAACGCGGAAUGUUGCCCUGGUCGCCGCCGCGGUGGGGCGCGGGCCCGGAGGAGGCGCCCGAGGGACCAGGCCUUCCGGCGGGCAAGGACCAGGGCGAGCCCUGGAGCGCCGGAGCGGACGCCCCCAGGGAGCUGGGGACACCCCCAUGGGACAGGUGAGGGGCUCGGACGGAGCCGUGGGGGGACAGCGACUGGGGGCCUCCAUGCCUUCACCACGCGCUCUACGGAGGCUUCUCCAUUGUCCCUGCUGGAGAUUGGGUCCCUCGGUCUCCCUUGCACCAGGCACCCUUGGGCUCCAGGGGAGGGUGCGUGGGGGCGGUGUGGCUGCAGCCUCAGUCCCUGCCCCUCCAGCCCACAGCCCCCAUCCCGUAGCCCUUCCUGGAUCUGGAGAGAGCAGCUGCUGCUGCCCCACCACCUGCCAGGCCCGGCCACUGAGCAGCCCCCCGGAGCCCCAGAUCCCCGUUCCCCCCAGGUGGCCUGGGAGGUGGCCCCCUCGAGGAUGACUCCACUAGCGCCCUGGGACCCCAAGUAUGAAGCCAAAGCAGGACCUCGGCCGGUGUGGGGGGCCAACUGUAGCUCAGGAGCCUCGUUCUCAGGCCGGACGCUGUGUCACCCCUCAUUCUGGCCGCUGUAUGAAGCAGCCUCGGGCAGGGGUCUCAGGCCCGUGGCCCCUGCCACAGGGCACUGGAAUGGACAGCAGGCGCCCCCAGAUGCAGGGUUCCCGGUGGUGUGCUGUGAAGAUGUCUUCCUCUCGGACCCUCUGCUGCCCCGGGGGCAGCGUGUUCCCCUGUACCUGUCCAAGGCCCCCCAGCAGAUGAUGGGCUCCCUGAAACUGCUGCCGCCGCCCCCCAUCAUGUCUGCCAGGGUGCUCCCCCGCCCAUCACCCUCCCGGGGCCCCUCCACUGCCUGGCUCAGCGGGCCGGAGCUGAUCGCUCUCACUGGCCUGCUGCAGAUGAGCCAGGGGGAGCCUAGGCCCAGCUCCUCCGCGGUUGGCCCCCCAGACCAUACCUCUGACCCACCCAGCCCCUGUGGUAGCCCCAGCAGUUCUCAGGGUGCUGACCUCUCUCUCCCACAGACCCCAGACACCCAUUGUCCAUAGCCUUCUCAGGGCAGAGUGGGCUGGUUGUGUUGACAAUAAAACAGUGUUGGUUUGCAAAA